AGAUAAUUAGCUCCUUUAUAACUAAAACCCAUAUUUACUAUUAUUAAAUUUAAAAAAGAAAUAGGAAAAAAAUCAUUCCCUGCACAAGGAGUUUUCAGAUCCAGAGUGUCAUAGUUAUUCAUUUUGGAAGUUGAUUUUUGGCUAAAUAAAAAGGUUUAUGGAAUGAUGGCCAUCCAAUGCAGAAUCAACUUUAGCAGAUGCAUUUGGAAAAAAUUCCAAGUGUUUAUCAUGAUGUCAACACAUUAUCUUCACUCAUAAGGACUGUAGAGCUAACGGAGUGUCUCCUAAGACAUCAAAUUCAUAUUAAGUUCUAUUUAAAAAGAGUUUCUUCUGUGGUUUCAUCUUUGCAAGAAAAGAAAAAUUAUACCACUUAUCAAGAACUGACAUUUUCUUUCAAUAUUGAAUUUUGCUUCAUGAUCCAAAACCUAGUUGUAAAAUUGAGCCCCAUAUAUGAGAAGAAAUGUCCAACGCCACCCUACUGACAGCGUUCAUCCUCACGGGCCUUCCCCAUGCCCCAGGGCUGGACGCCCCCCUCUUUGGAAUCUUCCUGGUGGUUUACGUGCUCACUGUGCUGGGGAACCUCCUCAUCCUGCUGGUGAUCAGGGUGGAUUCUCACCUCCACACCCCCAUGUACUACUUCCUCACCAACCUGUCCUUCAUUGACAUGUGGUUCUCCACUGUCACGGUGCCCAAAAUGCUGAUGACCUUGGUGUCCCCAAGCGGCAGGACUAUCUCCUUCCACAGCUGCGUGGCUCAGCUCUAUUUUUUCCACUUCCUGGGGAGCACCGAGUGUUUCCUCUACACAGUCAUGUCCUAUGAUCGCUACCUGGCCAUCAGUUACCCGCUCAGGUACACCAACAUGAUGACUGGGCGCUCGUGUGCCCUCCUGGCCACCGGCACUUGGCUCAGUGGCUCUCUGCACUCUGCUGUCCAGACCAUAUUGACUUUCCAUUUGCCCUACUGUGGACCCAACCAGAUCCAGCACUACUUCUGUGACGCACCGCCCAUCCUGAAACUGGCCUGUGCAGACACCUCAGCCAACGAGAUGGUCAUCUUUGUGAAUAUUGGGCUAGUGGCCUCGGGCUGCUUUGUCCUGAUAGUGCUGUCCUAUGUGUCCAUCGUCUGUUCCAUCCUGCGGAUCCGCACCUCAGAGGGGAGGCACAGAGCCUUUCAGACCUGUGCCUCCCACUGUAUCGUGGUCCUUUGCUUCUUUGGCCCUGGUCUUUUCAUUUACCUGAGGCCAGGCUCCAGGGACGCCUUGCAUGGGGUUGUGGCCGUUUUCUACACCACGCUGACUCCUCUUUUCAACCCUGUUGUGUACACCCUGAGAAACAAGGAGGUAAAGAAAGCUCUGUUGAAGCUGAAAAAUGGGUCAGUAUUUGCUCAGGGUGAAUAGUUAAGAAAGGCCAUAUAUGGCUAACUUUUCUUUUUUUAUUUGUAAUUAAAUUAAACCUUCAACAUAAGCAUUAUACUUGAAUGGAGCAUUUCAAUUAUUCAGUCUUAAUUUUUAAUUGGACAGUUAAUUAAUUUUUCAUUUUUUUCUGCAGAGUGUUUGUUAGAAUCCUAGUUAAAGCAGCCAUUUCACGGUGAUAAUCUAAGAGAAAGGAUAAUAGUCUAUUCUUUUCACGUUCCAUUAAGUAAUCAGAAAAGUAAUUUAUUUUCUUAUAUAAAUAUUUUCCAGAAUUGUUAUUCAGUAUAAUGUUCUUACAGUUUAUUUUGUGUCAUUUAAGUCAAAGCCUUAUAAAAAUCUUUUCAUGUUUUAAACUUUCUAUAUUGAAAAAUUCAUUAUAGCAUUCAUAAAUAACUACAUAAUUUAAUAUCCAUAAGAUAAAAUUUUUACUUUAGAAAAUACUAGACAAAAAGGCUUGGUUCUCAAGAAGAAUGGCUUUAUUCACAUUCAUGGGCCAAUAAAAACCAUAUAACUCUUUAAUAUUUUUUUCUUACUUUGGCCUGAAAGAUUUCUGAGAGUAAAUAUUUGUCCAUUUAUGCACUGUAUACACUGUACACAUUGUAUUGGUCUCUGAUGACAACUAUCUAGACUUUCCUUCCAUAUUUGUGGAGCUGCCAAUCUCUUAUCCUCAAUGGCAAGUUUCCAUUUUCAGCAAUUUUAAAAUUAUUUUUAUAAGUACCAGAGGAUAAAUAAUAAAUAUACAAAAAUGAUCAAAUAAUCUUAGAGACAAAAAUAUGCAGUCAAAAACUGUUAAGAGUAUCCCUUAAUUUAGAAUAAAGUACUAGAUAAUAUUUCCCAUGUAAUUAGACUAUGUCUGCAAGUCACAUUCGUUUGUUUGACUUAAAGUAUAUGAAAUGGACUCUGUACACUCUCUGGGUAGGUAAGGCUCAGACCAUGAACCUUAUAAUCUGUCAUCCAAAUAAAUACAUAUAUUUAAAGUGUAAAUAAAUUUUUCUCAAAAUAAAUGUUUAAUUUAAAUACCACAGGUAUCCUGGUCAUGCCAACUCUGCCUAGCAUAGCAUGAAGAGUAAAAGAAAACUAGAAGGCAGCUGCUAGAACUGAAAAGCAUUUCUCAAACUCCUCAGAUUUGCAGCAGCUGCAUUUCAAAGAUGCUUUAGCAAGAAUGCUCCUUUGUGCCAACUUUCCAUAUCUUGCUCCAAGUAAACUGUGCGGUGAUAUUGAGAAGAAAAACAUACUAACUUGGUAAGCAUGAGCUACAUAAACCAUGACACAGUACAUGAAGCAUGAACUACAUAAACCAUGAUCAGUAUAAGAGGUAAAUUUUUGGUUUUCACACCAAGAAACCAGAUUGCUAUGGACCAAUUAUAUAAUUCAGCUCAUUUCUCAAAGGAAAAAACUGAGGUAGACAUAAACCAAAAUUACUUAGUCAUUGGAUUCACUUGGAUUCUUACACUUCUCUGUAACAUCACGCUGUUAUAUCUAACUUACCAUUACCUAAAAUGUUAUGGGAUAUUUAUUGGGUGUUAAGUCACAUGCUAAACAGUAGAUACGCAAAAACAAUAGACAAGGUCUCUGCAUUCACCAAAGUCAUUGUCUGGCAAGGGGGAAAAAUAUGUUGCAUUGUCCAGGUUACAUUGUUGUAAGUGCAAUGGAUGCCCAAGGAGAGAUUCAUUAUUAGUUUUGACUUGGAAAGAUGCUAAAGGAUUCAAAAUACUAUGGCAAUAUGUAUCACACACAACCAUUUUGAAAGUAAAUUAUUGAUAAACAUAUAUAAGAAGAAUGUCAGUCUUUAUUUAAUUGAAAAUGUUGUUGAAAUAAUUUUAGAAUCGCAUGAAGUUGUAAGAAAUAACACAGUGAUAGUUCUUGUUAUACCUUGCCCAGUUUCCCCCAAUGGUAACAGUUAGCAAAAUUGUAGUGCAAUAUCACAACUGGGAUAUUGACAUUAUUAUAAUCCACAAAUCUUAUUCAGAUUUUUCUAGUUUUACUCACGUGUAUGUGUGUGUAUUUGUUAAAUACUAUACAGUUUUAACACCAGUGU